GUCUCACUCUGUCACCCAGGUUGGAGUGCAGUGGCACAGUCUUGGCUCACUGCAACCUCAGCCUCCCAGGUUCAAGUGAUUCUCCUGCCUCAUCCUCCCAAGUAACUGGGAUUACAGGUGCCUGCUACCAUGCUCACCUAAUUUUUGUAUUUUUAGUAGAGAUGGGGUUUCACCAUGUUGCCCCAGCUGGUCUUGAACUCCUGACGUCAAGUGAUCUGCCUGCCUACAUUUUCUUAUAAUACUUUAAAUUUCUAAGGGACAGUAGAGAAGUACCUUUUUAUUUCUUAUUUUGGUAAUUUCUUAUUUUUCUUCGUCAGUCUAGUUAAAGGUUUGUCCAUUUUGUUGAUCUUUUCAAAGAAUAAUCUUGUUUCAUUGAUUUUCUUUGUUUUUUUGUUUUCAUUUCAUUUAUUUAUGGUUUAAUUUUUUUUGUUAUUUCUGCUUGCUUUUGGUUAGUUUGUUAUCAUUGUUUAAAUGUCUUAAGAUGGAAAUUUAAGUUACUGAUUUGAUACCUUCCUCUUCUCUUCUUUUCUUUUCUUUCUACAUAGGUACCUAAAGCCACACAUUUCUCUACAAGCAUUGCUUUAGCUGGAUUCCAUAAAUUAUGCUAUGGAACAAAUAUCCUAUAUUAUUCCAAUAGAUGAGAAACUGUACACUGUGCACCUUAAACAAAGAUAUUUUUUAGCAGAUAAUUUUAUGAUCUAUUUGUACAAUCAAGGAUCUAUGAAUACUUAUUCUUCAGAUAUUCAGACUCAAUGCUACUAUCAAGGAAAUAUUGAAGGAUAUCCAGAUUCCAUGGUCACACUCAGCACGUGCUCUGGACUAAGAGGAAUACUGCAAUUUGAAAAUGUUUCUUAUGGAAUUGAGCCUCUGGAAUCUGCAGUUGAAUUUCAGCAUGUUCUUUACAAAUUAAAGAAUGAAGACAAUGAUAUUGCAAUUUUUAUUGACAGAAGCCUGAAAGAACAACCAAUGGAUGACAACAUUUUUAUAAGUGAAAAAUCAGAACCAGCUGUUCCAGAUUUAUUUCCUCUUUAUCUAGAAAUGCAUAUUGUGGUGGACAAAACUUUGUAUGAUUACUGGGGCUCUGAUAGCAUGAUAGUAACAAAUAAAGUCAUCGAAAUUGUUGGCCUUGCAAAUUCAAUGUUCACCCAAUUUAAAGUUACUAUUGUGCUGUCAUCAUUGGAGUUAUGGUCAGAUGAAAAUAAGAUUUCUACAGUUGGUGAGGCAGAUGAAUUAUUGCAAAAAUUUUUAGAAUGGAAACAAUCUUAUCUUAACCUAAGGCCUCAUGAUAUUGCAUAUCUACUAAUUUAUAUGGAUUAUCCUCGUUAUUUGGGAGCAGUGUUUCCUGGAACAAUGUGUAUUACUCGUUAUUCUGCAGGAGUUGCAUUGUACCCCAAGGAGAUAACUCUGGAGGCAUUUGCAGUUAUUGUCACCCAGAUGCUGGCACUCAGUCUGGGAAUAUCAUAUGACGACCCAAAGAAAUGUCAAUGUUCAGAAUCCACCUGUAUAAUGAAUCCAGAAGUUGUGCAAUCCAAUGGUGUGAAGACUUUUAGCAGUUGCAGUUUGAGGAGCUUUCAAAAUUUCAUUUCAAAUGUGGGUGUCAAAUGUCUUCAGAAUAAGCCACAAAUGCAAAAAAAAUCUCCGAAACCAGUCUGUGGCAAUGGCAGAUUGGAGGGAAAUGAAAUCUGUGAUUGUGGUACUGAGGCUCAAUGUGGACCUGCAAGCUGUUGUGAUUUUCGAACUUGUGUACUGAAAGACGGAGCAAAAUGUUAUAAAGGACUGUGCUGCAAAGACUGUCAAAUUUUACAAUCAGGCGUUGAAUGUAGGCCGAAAGCACAUCCUGAAUGUGACAUCGCUGAAAAUUGUAAUGGAAGCUCACCAGAAUGUGGUCCUGACAUAACUUUAAUCAAUGGACUUUCAUGCAAAAAUAAUAAGUUUAUUUGUUAUGACGGAGACUGCCAUGAUCUCGAUGCACGUUGUGAGAGUGUAUUUGGAAAAGGUUCAAGAAAUGCUCCAUUUGCCUGCUAUGAAGAAAUACAAUCUCAAUCAGACAGAUUUGGGAACUGUGGUAGGGAUAGAAAUAACAAAUAUGUGUUCUGUGGAUGGAGGAAUCUUAUAUGUGGAAGAUUAGUUUGUACCUACCCUACUCGAAAGCCUUUCCAUCAAGAAAAUGGUGAUGUGAUUUAUGCUUUCGUACGAGAUUCUGUAUGCAUAACCGUAGACUACAAAUUGCCUCGAACAGUUCCAGAUCCACUGGCUGUCAAAAAUGGCUCUCAGUGUGAUAUUGGGAGGGUUUGUGUAAAUCGUGAAUGUGUAGAAUCAAGGAUAAUUAAGGCUUCAGCACAUGUUUGUUCACAACAGUGUUCUGGACAUGGAGUGUGUGAUUCCAGAAACAAGUGCCAUUGUUCGCCAGGCUAUAAGCCUCCAAACUGCCAAAUACGUUCCAAAGGAUUUUCCAUAUUUCCUGAGGAAGAUAUGGGUUCAAUCAUGGAAAGAGCAUCUGGGAAGACUGAAAACACCUGGCUUCUAGGUUUCCUCAUUGCUCUUCCUAUUCUCAUUGUAACAACCGCAAUAGUUUUGGCAAGGAAACAGUUGAAAAAGUGGUUCGCCAAGGAAGAGGAAUUCCCAAGUAGCGAAUCUAAAUCGGAAGGUAGCACACAGACAUAUGCCAGCCAAUCCAGCUCAGAAGGCAGCACUCAGACAUAUGCCAGCCAAACCAGAUCAGAAAGCAGCAGUCAAGCUGAUACUAGCAAAUCCAAAUCAGAAGAUAGUGCUGAAGCAUAUACUAGCAGAUCCAAAUCACAGGACAGUACCCAAACACAAAGCAGUAGUAACUAGUGAUUCCUUCAGAAGGCAACGGAUAACAUCGAGAGUCUCGCUAAGAAAUGAAAAUUCUGUCUUUCCUUCCGUGGUCACAGCUGAAAGAAACAAUAAAUUGAGUGUGGAUCAAUUUGCA